AAUCAGAGGUUUCUGCUGCAGACAUGCCCCACCAGACCCUUAGUCAGACCAAGAAGAAUCCGAGUUUGAUAUCCUGCUUCAUAUUUAUUGGAGCUGGGAGUACUGGAGCAGCAUGGUAUGUCUUGUGUCUGGCAUCUUUCAGUCCAGAUGUUAGUUGGGCCAGAAACAAUAACCCAGAACCCUGGAACAAACUGAGUCCCAAUGAUCAAUACAAGUCCUACUCAGUGAAUGUAGAUUACAGCAAACUGAAGAAAGAAGGCCCAGAUUUCUAA